ACGGACUGGCUAGGCGCUGGUGAGGGGGCGGCGGUCCCAGCAGCAGGCAUGGGAGUGGCGGCGCGGCCCCCAGCCCUGCGGCACUGGUUCAGCCACUCAAUUCCUCUCGCUAUCUUCGCGCUGCUGCUGCUUUAUCUCAGUGUUCGGAGCCUAGGUGAGCUGCCCCUUCCCUCACUUGCUCCGGGAGGAAGCCCGGAAUCCAGGCCCUCACGACUCAAGCCUCUUUCUCGAGCCCUCACCGCUCCGCUUCUCCUCUACCCAGGCGCCCGCUCGGGCUGCGGACCCAGGGCGCAGCCCUGCGUUCCAGGGGAAACGGCGCCCUUCCAGGUCCGGCAGGAGUCGGGAACCCUGGAGGCCCCGGAGAGGAAACAGCCUCCGUGUCUGGGCCCUCGGGGGAUGCUGGGCCGCAUGAUGAGGCGGUUCCACGCCAGUCUGAAACCCGAAGGGGAUGUGGGGCUGUCGCCGUACCUGGCGGGAUGGAGGGCACUCGUCGAGUUCCUGACUCCCCUCGGCUCCGUCUUCGCCUUCGCCACUAGGGAGGCCUUCACCAAGGUGACAGACCUGGAGGCUCGGGUGCACGGCCCGGACGCGGAGCACUACUGGUCGCUGGUGGCCAUGGCGGCGUGGGAGCGGAGGGCGGGACUGCUGGAGCAGCCGGGGGCGGCCCCCCGGGACCCGACCCGGAGCUCGGGCUCUCGCACGCUGCUCCUGCUGCACCGCGCGCUGCGCUGGUCCCAGCUCUGCCUCCACCGGGUGGCGACCGGCGCGCUGGGAGGCCCGGACGCGGGCGUGCAGUGCAGCGACGCCUACCGUGCGGCCCUGGGUCCGCAUCACCCCUGGCUGGUCCGACAGACCGCCCGCCUCGCCUUCCUCGCCUUCCCGGGUCGCCGCCGCCUGCUGGAGCUGGCGUGUCCCGGAGCCACCGAGGCGGAGGCGCGGGCCGCGCUGGUCCGGGCCGCCGGCACCUUGGAGGAUGUCUACAACCGCACCCAGAGCCUGCUGGCCGAGCGCGGCCUGCUCCAGCUGGCCUAAGACGGCGGCUGCGGGGACCGGCGGGAACGGAGCGGACCGCCCGGGGUGGGGCCGCGCAGCCCGGGGUCAGUCCUGCAGCCCGCGCCGCGGCCGCCUCCGUAUCCCGCCUCUUCCGUGACGUCGCCGCGGCGAGGGCCGCCCCCGGCAGGGAAUGGCGUUGAGCUCCCUCUGUCCGCAGUCUCGGAAAGACGGGAGGAGCUGUGAGGAAUAAAAAAGCAAUAUUUGGCAGCGUCGACGUAGGGCGUUUUGUGUGAUGACGACAGGCGCUUAAGGGAAAUAAAAAACGAAGGUGA